CCUUUCGUUGCCUGAUCGCCGCCAUCAUGGGUCGCAUGCAUGCUCCCGGGAAGGGCCUGUCCCAGUCGGCUUUACCCUAUCGACGCAGCGUCCCCACUUGGUUGAAGUUGACAUCUGACGACGUGAAGGAGCAGAUUUACAAACUGGCCAAGAAGGGCCUUACUCCUUCACAGAUCGGUGUAAUCCUGAGAGAUUCACAUGGUGUUGCACAAGUACGUUUUGUGACAGGCAAUAAAAUUUUAAGAAUUCUUAAGUCUAAGGGACUUGCUCCUGAUCUUCCUGAAGAUCUCUACCAUUUAAUUAAGAAAGCAGUUGCUGUUCGAAAGCAUCUUGAGAGGAACAGAAAGGAUAAGGAUGCUAAAUUCCGUCUGAUUCUAAUAGAGAGCCGGAUUCACCGUUUGGCUCGAUAUUAUAAGACCAAGCGAGUCCUCCCUCCCAAUUGGAAAUAUGAAUCAUCUACAGCCUCUGCCCUGGUCGCAUAAAUUUGUCUGUGUACUCAAGCAAUAAAAUGAUUGUUUAACUAAAAG